AGUCACCCGCAGCAGGCGUGCAGUUUCCCGGCUCUCCGCGCGGCCGGGGAAGGUCAGCGCCGUAAUGGCGUUCUUGGCGUCGGGACCCUACCUGACCCAUCAGCAAAAGGUGUUGCGGCUUUAUAAGCGGGCGCUACGCCACCUCGAGUCGUGGUGCGUCCAGAGAGACAAAUACCGAUACUUUGCUUGUUUGAUGAGAGCCCGGUUUGAAGAACAUAAGAAUGAAAAGGAUAUGGCGAAGGCCACCCAGCUGCUGAAGGAGGCCGAGGAAGAAUUCUGGUACCGUCAGCAUCCACAGCCAUACAUCUUCCCUGACUCUCCUGGGGGCACCUCCUAUGAGAGAUACGAUUGCUACAAGGUCCCAGAAUGGUGCUUAGAUGACUGGCAUCCUUCUGAGAAGGCAAUGUAUCCUGAUUACUUUGCCAAGAGAGAACAGUGGAAGAAACUGCGGAGGGAAAGCUGGGAACGAGAGGUUAAGCAGCUGCAGGAGGAAACGCCACCUGGUGGUCCUUUAACUGAAGCUUUGCCCCCUGCCCGAAAGGAAGGUGAUUUGCCCCCACUGUGGUGGUAUAUUGUGACCAGACCCCGGGAGCGGCCCAUGUAGAAAGAGAGAGACCUCAUCUUUCAUGCUUGCAAGUGAAAUAUGUUACAGAACAUGCACUUGCCCUAAUAAAAAAUCAGUGAAAUGGUC